GGAGUGGCCGGGAGAUGAUGGCUGAUGAAGAGGAAGAAGUCAAGCCGAUCUUGCAGAAAUUGCAGGAACUCGUGGAUCAGCUCUACUCAUUUCGAGACUGCUAUUUCGAGACACAUAGUGUUGAGGAUGCUGGGAGGAAGCAACAGGAUGUGCAGAAGGAGAUGGAGAAAACCCUACAGCAGAUGGAAGAAGUAGUGGGUUCUGUCCAGGGCAAGGCACAAGUUCUAAUGCUAACUGGGAAAGCACUAAAUGUGACUCCUGACUAUAGCCCUAAGGCUGAGGAGCUUCUGUCAAAGGCUGUGAAGCUGGAGCCCGAGCUGGUGGAAGCCUGGAACCAGCUGGGUGAGGUGUACUGGAAAAAAGGGGAUGUUGCAGCUGCCCACACCUGCUUCUCAGGAGCCCUCACCCAUUGCAGGAACAAAGUCUCCUUGCAAAACCUGUCAAUGGUGCUUCGUCAGCUGCGGACUGACACUGAAGAUGAACAUUCUCACCAUGUCAUGGACAGUGUCCGACAGGCUAAGUUGGCUGUUCAGAUGGAUGUCCAUGAUGGCCGCUCCUGGUAUAUUCUUGGGAAUUCAUAUCUUUCCCUUUACUUCUCUACUGGCCAGAACCCUAAGAUCUCCCAGCAAGCCCUCAGUGCCUAUGCCCAAGCAGAGAAAGUUGACAGAAAAGCUUCUAGCAAUCCUGACCUUCAUCUGAACAGGGCGACGUUGCAUAAAUAUGAAGAGAGUUAUGGGGAGGCCCUGGAGGGCUUCUCUCGGGCUGCAGCCCUGGACCCUGCCUGGCCAGAGCCCCGGCAACGAGAGCAACAACUUCUGGAAUUCCUGGAUAGAUUAACCAGCCUCCUUGAGAGUAAGGGAAAGGUGAAGACCAAAAAGCUGCAGAGCAUGCUGGGAAGCUUGCGCCCAGCCCAUCUAGGCCCUUGCAGUGAUGGGCACUAUCAGUCAGCCUCUGGGCAGAAAGUGACCCUGGAGCUCAAGCCACUGAGUACGCUUCAGCCUGGGGUGAACAGCGGUGCCGUCAUCCUGGGAAAGGUGGUAUUUAGCCUCACCACAGAGGAGAAAGUCCCCUUUACAUUUGGCCUGGUAGAUUCAGAUGGACCUUGCUAUGCAGUGAUGGUGUACAAUAUAGUGCAGAGCUGGGGAGUGCUCAUUGGAGACUCUGUAGCCAUUCCUGAGCCCAACCUGCGGCUUCACCGAAUUCAGCACAAAGGAAAGGACUAUUCCUUUUCCAGUGUUCGAGUGGAGACGCCCCUCCUGCUAGUGGUGAAUGGGAAGCCUCAGGGAUCCAGCAGCCAGGCUGUUGCCACAGUGGCAUCGCGACCACAGUGUGAAUGACCUUUGACUUGCAUGCUCAACAGGGAGUGGAGGAGAGGAGACAAGGCUCUGGACAGCCGGUCCAGCCACAUCCAGUGAUUCAGCAGGGAUGGGAGGAAUGUUUUAAAUGAAGACUUUCUCUUUCCCUGCCUGUAUUACACUUCGUAUCUCUUCUCUCUCCUCUGUCCUCAUCAUGUUCCAGCUCUCUACAGGGCCACAUACUCUUCUGGCAUAUCUCUCCUGUCUCUUCCACUGCUCUCUAUGUUUUAAGCAAAGAGCAUGGAAUUGGUAGAAGUCUUGGGAUCUUGCCAUGGGACAGAGUCCCCAAGGUUCCUGUUGUUGCCUCCUUCCUAAGCCUCAUAUGUAUAUAUCAGUUCAGUAUUUAUUGCUAAAGGAGGGGGCUUAAUUUUGUAAUGGCUUUUAUUUUUAGCAAUUUUUAUUUUUAUUUUUGAACUUUAGGUCCUUCCUCUUCUUUGGGGCUGGAACAGAAUUAAAUUUGUUUGGAAAAAAAAAAAAACACCACGUAGUUUGGCCUGCUUUAUUCUCCCUAGGCCUGUAUUCUUUGUUUUAGGAUCACUUCAAUUUAUUGGAGUAAUACCCCCAUUUUUUUCUUUAUACAAAGCAGUUUAUUUCUCUCCCAGUUAAAAGAAUUCCGACAAUAGACAGCCCCAGGCAGGAAUGGCAACUCCACAAAGUUGCUAGAGACCAGCUUUCUUCCAUUUUCCCAUUCUGUCAUUCCCUAGGGGUGGUCUUCACUAUGGUCCAAGAUGACAGAGCAAUACUGUUCUAAUAGUGUUACUAGGCUGAAGGACCAGAGAGAGUUAGAUAAAUCCUCAGUUUCUUUAGAGUCUAGUGACAUGUUUUAUAACAGUUUAUCUUAAUAUCCUUGUGGUAAAAUGGAGAAAUGUGAGUGAGGAUUAAUAACCAAUUGAAUUGGCCUGGCACGGUGGCUCAGCCUGUAAUCCCACCACUUUGGGAGUCCAAGGCGGGUGGAUCACGAGGUCAGGAGUUCAAGAUCAGCCUGGCCAAGAUGGUGAAACUCCGUCUCUACUAAAAAUACAAAAAUUAGCUGGGCGUGGUGGCAGGCACCUGUAAUCACAGCUACUGGGGAGGCUGAGGCAGAGAAUUGCUUGAACCUGGGAAGUGGAGGUUGCAGUGAGCCGAUAUCAUGCCACUGCACUCCAGCAUGGGCGACAGAGCGAGACUCCGUCUCAAACAGCAACAACAACUGAAUGGCUGUAAUACAUUAAUGUAUACAGAUGAAUUGAGAAGUCUUCUAGUGAAAUGGCUCAGAUCUUUGUUCUUGGUCCAGUCCUGUUCAGUUUUUGAUCAGUGCCUUGAAUAUCAUUGAUGACUCAUUAAAUUUAUAAAGAGUGCAGAGGCCUCCUCAGAGAAUGGAUGGUAGAAAUGCAUUGAUGAGAGAAGUUUUAUCUAUCUAUCUGUCUAUCUAUCUAUCUAUCUAUCUGUCUCUAUCUAAGAAGUCAUAAAGGCUGAGUCUAAUAAGAUAAAAUUUUCAGUCCAUUCUUUUGGUCCAAAAAGGCUUACAUUCUCAGGUAUAGCUUCAACAUCAUAUAUGAAUAUUACUAAGAAUCUUAGUAGAUAAGCUAAAGUCAGUAUGAGUAACCAGUCUGAUAUAGUUUGCAAGAACACUCUUCAUGGACUGCACCAAAAAAACCUAUGGUAGCAAGAGACAGUUUUUAUUAGAAGUACUGUCUGUUAUACCACAUAUGGAGUCUUAAAUUAGUUUUGGGUGUCAUUUUGAGGCCUAGAGUCAUAGAAGAGUGAUUAGGAGCUUGUGGGGUAUAAAAAUAACUUGAGAAUUGGCUGAAAGCAACUAGGGAAGAUGGGGGUAGUAGUAUGUGUAAACAUUUGAGGCAGUAGAGAUGUGGGACCCAAAUACUGUUCCCCUUUUACUCAAAUUCUGAGAUGAGUUGACAUGUUCUGUGUAGGGCUAGAGAGUAGAAAAAUGGCCAGUAGGUGGUAGCCACAGAGAAGCAGUGCGUACAAACAAGUAAGUAUGCAAAAUUUGUACAUACGGUUUCAGGAAUAACUAGAAUACCCAUAAAAUAUCCACCUGCCUUAAAAACUAGAACAUCAUUGAUAACUUGGAAGCCCUUGCAUACCUCUCCAUGAUCUCAUUUGUCUUCACAGCUAUAUAAAUCUCAUUGUAUGAUUAUACCAUAAUUUAUUCAUCCUGUUGUUAAAGGAUAUUUGGGUUUCCAGUUUUUCUUUUUUUACUACCAAAGCACUACAUUAUUAAUAUUCUUGUAUAUGUCCUGAUAUGUAAGUGCAAAAGUUUCUUUUACAGCAAUGGCUCUUGAAGAGUGGUUCCCAGACCAGCAGCAUCAGCAUCCCUUGGAACUUCUUUGAAAUGCAAAUUCUCAAGCCCCCUACCCAGACUUACUGAAUUCAAAACUAUGUGGGAGGAGCCCAGCAAUCUGUGUUUCGCAAACCCUCCAGGUGACUCUGAUGCACAGUAAAAUUUGAGAACCACUGUUUAAGAGUAUUGACAUAGAAUGGAAUUGCUGGAUCAUAGAGUAUAUACAUGUUCAACUUUUUUGAGAAGCACUAAACAUUUCCAAAGUGCUUAUAUUAGUUUAUGUCUCUACUAUCAAUAGAUGAGUCACCCCAAUGCUCCCCAUCCUCUUCUGUGCUUGGUAUUAUCUUUUAGGUAUUGCAAAUACAGGAGAUUUGAGUAUUAUUUCCUUGUGGCCUUAAUUUGCAUUUCUGAUUAUUAAUGAGCUUGAGCAUCUUUUCAUAUAUUUAGAAGCCACUAAUAUUUUCUCUCGGUAAAAUGCCUAUUCGAGUCUUUGCACACUGCUGUAUUGGAUGUCAAAUUGAUUUAUAUAUUCCCUGUACUAAUCGUUUGUCUACAUACAGUUUUAUCCUGUUUUUUUUUUUAUUCUAUUGGGUCUUUUGCUGAACAGAAGUUCUUAAUUUCAAUGUCAUUGAAUUUAUCCAUCUUUUAUGAUAAUGCUUUUUGUGUUUUAAGAGGUUCUUAGCUCUCCUAAAGUCAUAAGGACAUUUUCCCUCUACUGCUUUAUGAAGUUAUUUUGUCCUUUUCUUACAGUAUGACUUUAUUUUAUGUUAUGUACGGAUAUAAUUUUUUUCAUAAUGAGUAAAUAGCCCAGCACCUUUUAUUAAAGAAUCAAUCCUUUCCCUACUGAUCUUUAAAGCCCAGUCUGUCUUUUUCUUUUUUUGAAAUUGUCUAGCUUUUUAAUUUUUACCAACCAGAUGAUUAUAAAAUAUCACAUAGUAGGCAUAAAUUACAUUUCUUUGUCCAUUCCUGUUUCUUUUUCUAUGAAAUCUCUGUUUUCUUUUGUCCAAUUUUUAUUGGGUUGUCUUCUUAUUGAUUCCUUACAUGUUCUGGAUACUAAUCCAUUAUAAAUUAUGUUUUUCAAAUAUAUUUAUCCAAAUCGCA